AGCGAGAGCGCGCGGAUCUCAGCGCGGGAGCAGUGCUUCUGCGGCAGGUGCUGCCCGGGGCCGGGGACUGGGGACUGGGGACUGCCGGGGCGGAAGACGCCGCUGCCCGCCUGCCACGGAGGGCAGGGAGGGCGGGCCUGACGGCUCCGCAGCCCGGAGAAGGGACGCCGGGUGGGGCCCCAGUGCGGAGCGUGCGGAGCCGCGCAGCACGUGGCGCGCACGGGCCAGGGAGCCUGAGGACCCUGCGGGGACCGGGACCCAAGCUGGGCGGGGCGGCCUGGCUCCCGGGCCUAAAACAGGCUGCGGUCACGUUGACCUCCGCAAGGGGCAGGCGAGUGGACGGGUGAUCCCCAUCGAUCUGGAGCCCGUGGACAAGGCCCACUGCCUGAGCCUGAACUAGGAGCACCUCCUAGGGACUGCCCAGGCUUGCUCUGCUCUGACCCUUCUGCUGGCCAGUCUGGGCACCUGCAGGCCCCUGAGGGAGGGAGCUGUCAGCCAGGGAAAACCGAGAACACCAUCACCAUGACAACCAGUCACCAGCCUCAGGACAGAUACAAAGCUGUCUGGCUUAUCUUCUUCAUGCUGGGUCUGGGAACGCUGCUCCCGUGGAAUUUUUUCAUGACGGCCACUCAGUAUUUCACAAACCGCCUGGACAUGUCCCAGAAUGUGUCCUUGGUCACUGCUGAACUGAGCAAGGACGCCCAGGCGUCAGCCGCCCCUGCAGCACCCUUGCCUGAGCGGAACUCUCUCAGUGCCAUCUUCAACAAUGUCAUGACCCUAUGUGCCAUGCUGCCCCUGCUGUUAUUCACCUACCUCAACUCCUUCCUGCAUCAGAGGAUCCCCCAGUCCGUACGGAUCCUGGGCAGCCUGGUGGCCAUCCUGCUGGUGUUUCUGAUCACUGCCAUCCUGGUGAAGGUGCAGCUGGAUGCUCUGCCCUUCUUUGUCAUCACCAUGAUCAAGAUCGUGCUCAUUAAUUCAUUUGGUGCCAUCCUGCAGGGCAGCCUGUUUGGUCUGGCUGGCCUUCUGCCUGCCAGCUACACGGCCCCCAUCAUGAGUGGCCAGGGCCUAGCAGGCUUCUUUGCCUCCGUGGCCAUGAUCUGCGCUAUUGCCAGUGGCUCGGAGCUAUCAGAAAGUGCCUUCGGCUACUUUAUCACAGCCUGUGCUGUUAUCAUUUUGACCAUCAUCUGUUACCUGGGCCUGCCCCGCCUGGAAUUCUACCGCUACUACCAGCAGCUCAAGCUUGAAGGACCCGGGGAGCAGGAGACCAAGUUGGACCUCAUUAGCAAAGGAGAGGAGCCAAGAGCAGGCAAAGAGGAAUCUGGAGUUUCAGUCUCCAACUCUCAGCCCACCAAUGAAAGCCACUCUAUCAAAGCCAUCCUGAAAAAUAUCUCAGUCCUGGCUUUCUCUGUCUGCUUCAUCUUCACUAUCACCAUUGGGAUGUUUCCAGCCGUGACUGUUGAGGUCAAGUCCAGCAUCGCAGGCAGCAGCACCUGGGAACGUUACUUCAUUCCUGUGUCCUGUUUCUUGACUUUCAAUAUCUUUGACUGGUUGGGCCGGAGCCUCACAGCUGUAUUCAUGUGGCCUGGGAAGGACAGCCGCUGGCUGCCAAGCCUGGUGCUGGCCCGGCUGGUGUUUGUGCCACUGCUGCUGCUGUGCAACAUUAAGCCCCGCCGCUACCUGACUGUGGUCUUCGAGCACGAUGCCUGGUUCAUCUUCUUCAUGGCUGCCUUUGCCUUCUCCAACGGCUACCUCGCCAGCCUCUGCAUGUGCUUCGGGCCCAAGAAAGUGAAGCCAGCUGAGGCAGAGACCGCAGGAGCCAUCAUGGCCUUCUUCCUGUGUCUGGGUCUGGCACUGGGGGCUGUUUUCUCCUUCCUGUUCCGGGCAAUUGUGUGACAAAGGAUGGACAGAAGGACUGCCUGCCUCCCUCCCUGUCUGCCUCCUGCCCCUUCCUUCUGCCAGGGGUGAUCCUGAGUGGUCUGGCGGUUUUUUCUUCUAACUGACUUCUGCUUUCCACGGCGUGUGCUGGGCCCGGAUCUCCAGGCCCUGGGGAGGGAGCCUCUGGACGGACAGUGGGGACAUUGUGGGUUUGGGGCUCAGAGUCGAGGGACGGGGUGUAGCCUCGGCAUUUGCUUGAGUUUCUCCACUCUUGGCUCUGACUGAUCCCUGCUUGUGCAGGCCAGUGGAGGCUCUUGGGCUUGGAGAACACGUGUGUCUCUGUGUAUGUGUCUGUGUGUCUGCGUCCGUGUCUGUCAGACUGUCUGCCUGUCCUGGGGUGGCUAGGAGCUGGGUCUGACCGUUGUAUGGUUUGACCUGAUAUACUCCAUUCUCCCCUGCGCCUCCUCCUCUGUGUUCUCUCCAUGUCCCCCUCCCAACUCCCCAUGCCCAGUUCUUACCCAUCAUGCACCCUGUACAGUUGCCACGUUACUGCCUUUUUUAAAAAUAUAUUUGACAGAAACCAGGUGCCUUCAGAGGCUCUCUGAUUUAAAUAAACCUUUCUUGUUUUUUUC